CUUUUUUAGCGCCAUCUGCUCGCGGCGCCGCCUCCUGCUCCUCCCGCUGCUGCUGCCGCUGCCGCCCUGAGUCACUGCCUGCGCAGCUCCGGCCGCCUGGCUCCCCAUACUAGUCGCCGAUAUUUGGAGUUCUUACAACAUGGCAGACAUUGACAACAAAGAACAGUCUGAACUUGAUCAAGAUUUGGAUGAUGUUGAAGAAGUAGAAGAAGAGGAAACUGGUGAAGAAACAAAACUCAAAGCACGUCAGCUAACUGUUCAGAUGAUGCAAAAUCCUCAGAUUCUUGCAGCCCUUCAAGAAAGACUUGAUGGUCUGGUAGAAACACCAACAGGAUACAUUGAAAGCCUGCCUAGGGUAGUUAAAAGACGAGUGAAUGCUCUCAAAAACCUGCAAGUUAAAUGUGCACAGAUAGAAGCCAAAUUCUAUGAGGAAGUUCACGAUCUUGAAAGGAAGUAUGCUGUUCUCUAUCAGCCUCUAUUUGAUAAGCGAUUUGAAAUUAUUAAUGCAAUUUAUGAACCUACGGAAGAAGAAUGUGAAUGGAAACCAGAUGAAGAAGAUGAGAUUUCGGAGGAAUUGAAAGAAAAGGCCAAGAUUGAAGAUGAGAAAAAAGAUGAAGAAAAAGAAGACCCCAAAGGAAUUCCUGAAUUUUGGUUAACUGUUUUUAAGAAUGUUGACUUGCUCAGUGAUAUGGUUCAGGAACACGAUGAACCUAUUCUGAAGCACUUGAAAGAUAUUAAAGUGAAGUUCUCAGAUGCUGGCCAGCCUAUGAGUUUUGUCUUAGAAUUUCACUUUGAACCCAAUGAAUAUUUUACAAAUGAAGUGCUGACAAAGACAUACAGGAUGAGGUCAGAACCAGAUGAUUCUGAUCCCUUUUCUUUUGAUGGACCAGAAAUUAUGGGUUGUACAGGGUGCCAGAUAGAUUGGAAAAAAGGAAAGAAUGUCACUUUGAAAACUAUUAAGAAGAAGCAGAAACACAAGGGACGUGGGACAGUUCGUACUGUGACUAAAACAGUUUCCAAUGACUCUUUCUUUAACUUUUUUGCCCCUCCUGAAGUUCCUGAGAGUGGAGAUCUGGAUGAUGAUGCUGAAGCUAUCCUUGCUGCAGACUUCGAAAUUGGUCACUUUUUACGUGAGCGUAUAAUCCCAAGAUCAGUGUUAUAUUUUACUGGAGAAGCUAUUGAAGAUGAUGAUGAUGAUUAUGAUGAAGAAGGUGAAGAAGCGGAUGAGGAAGGGGAAGAAGAAGGAGAUGAGGAAAAUGAUCCAGACUAUGACCCAAAGAAGGAUCAAAACCCAGCAGAGUGCAAGCAGCAGUGAAGCAGGAUGUAUGUGGCCUUGAGGAUAACCUGCACUGUAAUAGCCUAAACACAACUCUUAUUUACUUACAGCCUUAUGUUUUUGUAUUUUCUUGGUAGACUAGGUAAUUUUUUUUUAAAGGACAGGAAACUGAUAUUUUAAAGACCAAUUUGUUCUACCUAGCAUUUUAACUAGUUUUUCUGCCAGCUAUGUUGAAUGCACAAAUUCUGUCACGCAUGUUCAUUCAUUGCUACAUAAUUUGGUUCUUCUGGAAUAUUUUUAUGUAGCUCUUGGAGUACAGCUAUGAAAAUUAACAACUGUUAAAGGAAAUACCUUUUUUUUUUUUUUGUAAUUUUUUCCUUGAAGAACCAAAGUAUUUUUUCAGCUGGUUGUUGAAUAGGGUUAAGUCCGCUUGGAUUAGCUGUGCCUUUCAUUACUUUGUUACAGAAAUGCAGUGACUUAUACUAAGACAAUUUAUUGUUUAAAAAAAAAAUUGGCAAGACAACUAUAUGGUUAAGAAUUUCCAGUAUGACCACACCCAAUAACUGUUAUUAGAGUGUUAAUGGAUUAUUGUGUUUUAGGUGACAUAGUUAACUGUAAAGUAACCUGACUCAGUAUAGUUACUGGUACCACAGUGAGGUGAAUAAAACGGGAUUUUCAGAAGUUAGCCUGAAUUUAACUGUAUUUUUAAAUUUAACCUCCAUUAACUAAGCAUCUUUUCUUUGUGGUAGGGUCUACCUUCUGCUUCCCUGGAAAGGAUGAAUUUACAUCAUUUGACAAGCCUAUUUUCAAGUUAUUUGUUGUUUGUUUGCUUGUUUUUGUUUUUGCAGCUAAAAUAAAAAUUUCAAAUACAAUUUUAGUUCUUACAAGAUAAUGUCUUAAUUUUGUACCAAUUCAGGUAGAAGUAGAGGCCUACCUUGAAUUAAGGGUUAUACUCAGUUUUUAACACAUUGUUGAAGAAAAGGUACCAGCUUUGGAACGAGAUGCUAUACUAAUAAGCAAGUGUAAAAAAAAAAAAAAAAGAGGAAGAAAAUCUUAAGUGAUUGAUGCUGUUUUCUUUUAAAAAAAAAAAAAAAAAUUCAUUUUCUUUGGGUUAGAGCUAGAGAGAAGGCCCCAAGCUUCUAUGGUUUCUUCUAAUUCUUAUUGCUUAAAGUAUGAGUAUGUCACUUACCCGUGCUUCUGUUUACUGUGUAAUUAAAAUGGGUAGUACUGUUUACCUAACUACCUCAUGGAUGUGUUAAGGCAUAUUGAGUUAAAUCUCAUAUAAUGUUUCUCAAUCUUGUUAAAAGCUCAAAAUUUUGGGCCUAUUUGUAAUGCCAGUGUGACACUAAGCAUUUUGUUCACACCACGCUUUGAUAACUAAACUGGAAAACAAAGGUGUUAAGUACCUCUGUUCUGGAUCUGGGCAGUCAGCACUCUUUUUAGAUCUUUGUGUGGCUCCUAUUUUUAUAGAAGUGGAGGGAUGCACUAUUUCACAAGGUCCAAGAUUUGUUUUCAGAUAUUUUUGAUGACUGUAUUGUAAAUACUACAGGGAUAGCACUAUAGUAUUGUAGUCAUGAGACUUAAAGUGGAAAUAAGACUAUUUUUGACAAAAGAUGCCAUUAAAUUUCAGACUGUAGAGCCACAUUUACAAUACCUCAGGCUAAUUACUGUUAAUUUUGGGGUUGAACUUUUUUUUGACAGUGAGGGUGGAUUAUUGGAUUGUCAUUAGAGGAAGGUCUAGAUUUCCUGCUCUUAAUAAAAUUACAUUGAAUUGAUUUUUAGAGGUAAUGAAAACUUCCUUUCUGAGAAGUUAGUGUUAAGGUCUUGGAAUGUGAACACAUUGUUUGUAGUGCUAUCCAUUCCUCUCCUGAGAUUUUAACUUACUACUGGAAAUCCUUAACCAAUUAUAAUAGCUUUUUUUCUUUAUUUUCAAAAUGAUUUCCUUUGCUUUGAUUAGACACUAUGUGCUUUUUUUUUUUAACCAUAGUUCAUCGAAAUGCAGCUUUUUCUGAACUUCAAAGAUAGAAUCCCAUUUUUAAUGAACUGAAGUAGCAAAAUCAUCUUUUUCAUUCUUUAGGAAAUAGCUAUUGCCAAAGUGAAGGUGUAGAUAAUACCUAGUCUUGUUACAUAAAGGGGAUGUGGUUUGCAGAAGAAUUUUCUUUAUAAAAUUGAAGUUUUAAGGGACGUCAGUGUUUAUGCCAUUUUUCCAGUUCCAAAAUGAUUCCAUUCCAUUCUAGAAAUUUGAAGUAUGUAACCUGAAAUCCUUAAUAAAAUUUGGAUUUAAUUUUAUAAAAUGUACUGGUGAUAUUUUGGGUGUUUUUUUUUAAAUGAAUGUAUAUACUUUUUUUUUGAAGAGUGGAGAGUAGUGAUGUCUAGAGGGAGCUAUUUUGUGCUGAGGCCACUAUGUUCUGUAAAUAUAUAAUUUUAAGAGCAACCUCACAAUCCCUGCUAAGUGGAGUUUAUUAUUUGAAGACUAAAAUGGAAUUCCAUAGUUCCUGAUAGGUUAUAUUCUGGGUUAUUAUUCUGAGUUAUCUACAAACAUUUUUGAGAUUUGUCUUUACACUCUGAUUGUAGUUUCCAGCAGCCCAUGCACACUGCCAAGUAAGUCUCAUUUUUUCCUGUUAGAAAUGGUGAAAUAUCAUAUAAUCACUUAUAAAGAAAACUGAUAUGAAAAAAUUUUAGAGUUGUUUGCUUUAUGGUCACUCAAGUAGGGUAAGUGUUCCACAAAUUCCACAAGUUGAUAGUUUAACAUGGAUGUCUGAAAGCCACAUAUAUAAUUUCUUAGGAUUCUUAAAUUAGUAAAUCUAGCUUACUGAAGCAGUAUUAGCAUCACUAUUUUAGAUUGCAAAAAUACCUUAAUUGUGUGGAACUGGCUUGUAGAGUGGUACUUAAGAAAAAUGGGAUUCUACCUCUAUUUCUGUUUUAGCACACUUAAUCAGGAAAGGAUAUAUUAACUUUCAUAAAAAUAUUUUUGUUGUGUGAAUAGGUUAAUGAUAUGGUAAGGCCCCUAAAAUAACUGAAUUAAUUGUUUAUUGUAAUUGUAGGCCAUUCCCAUUAUUAAAAAUAAAGACAAAACUUGAAGUAACUGAAAAUCUUAUCGUGCUAUGUAGAAAUAUUGAACUAAUAUUCAAAUAUUUGAAUGCUUUGGUUUCAGGGAUUGGUUUAAAAUUGGAGUCCUUUUUUAUGGGUUAGUCUUACAAAAAUUUAAGCCUUUAUAUUUUUGACUUUAAAUCAAAACAAAUGUUAUUUUAAAUGUACAGAAUAGAUUGGUAGUGCAGAAGAGUGUAAGUUCUUCAUAGGAGCUUUAGAAAAGAGAAAUAUGUGCUAAUUCAGUUUUUUUUUAAUCUGCACUGUACAUAUAUACUUGGUAAUUAUGAGCUUGAUUUUGUUUUUGGAAAUAUGUGUUCAUAAUUUAGGUAAUUUGCUACUUAAAGCACUAAGUCUCUGAUACCUGAAAAGUACAUGUAAAUGGUGAUGGUGAAAUAAUACUGCAGUUAACUUAAUAGAUGUAUACUGGUGAUUUUUGUAUGCUGGAUUAAAACUCCAGAUAUUAAAAUAUAACCUGGAUAAAAAGCCAAGUUCUUGGACUGAUUGAGGAUCACUUACAUGACUUUACAGAAAUGGAAACAUCCUUGUUGGUAUAUGAAAUUAUUUUACUCAAGGAUAAGUAUUCAUAAGAAAUUUUGAUUGAUGUAUAUUUUCAAAAAUACAGUAUGCUUUGUAUCUUGUGUUUCUUCCUUUUGACAUCAUAUUGUCAGGUUUUCCAGUUUACAAAAAUUAAGUUAUUCACUAAAAUCUUAGUACAGACAGUCCCUGACUUAUAAUGGUUUGACUUAAGACUUCAGCUUUAUGAGUUUAUUGGAGUAUUAAACACAUCUUCUACUUAUGAUAUUUUUGACUUACAGUGGGCUUAUUGAGGCCCGACCAUGUCAUCCUCAAGCCAAGAGUCUGAAUAAAAGAAGAAAUGGGGUAUUUAGAAAUAAUAGAUUACUGGCGGGAAAUAAGUCAGUCUGGUUGUUUAAUUUUCCUAUGGGAAAUUGGGCAUUUUAAGUUUUGUGGAUCCUAGAACAAACUGAGUUUUAUUAUUUUGAAACCCAGGAUAAAAUAUUACAUAAAAGCAUUGCUUUUUAGUUUCUUACAUGUUUUAUCCAUUUAUUUUUAUUUUUGAGAUAGAGUCUUGCUCUGUUGCCCAGGCUGGAGUGCAGUGGCAUGAUCUCGGCUCACUACAGCUGUCAUCUCCCGGGUUCAAGCGAUUCUCGUGCCUCAGCAUUCCAAGUAGUCGGGAUUACAGGCGUGUGCCACUGAGCCCAGCUGAUUUUUGUACUUUUAGUAGAGAUGGGUUUUCACCAUGUUGGCCAGGCUGGUCUCGACCUCCUGACCUCCAGUGAUCCUCCCACCUCAGCCUCUCAAAGUGCUGGCCUCUCAAAAGUGCUGGGAUUACAAGCAUGAGCCACCACGCCCAGCCAGUUUCUUACAUGUUUUAAACUUAAAGCCAAAAAGAAGGAACUAGGAAUGUGUGAUUAAACGUGAGUGCCAGAAGUCGACAGAUCUCAUAUCCAGAGUUGAAGGUCUUAUUCAUAAUUUUAUCAUUCAUAAUGUAUUAGGCAAUUGCGGCUCUGGUAAAUUUCAUGAGGUUGUAAAAUAGUUGCUACCAGAAGGCUCAAAAUUUGUAUGAGCUUUUAGCUGAGAUUUUGAGAAUCUGUAGGAAUUUGUGAAGUGAGAGGAAGAACCUCUGAACGGUGAGCAGUUCAGGUGGAGGAACAGGAGGAAAUACAGGCAAAGGUCCCAGAACAGAACAAUUGAGGCUACAUUCAAGGAAUUGAGAUACCUGGAAAUACAGGUAGAAAUACAAGUGGCCAGUCCAUAGAAAGUUUAGCUGUGGAAGUCCUCUUAAUGGGUUUAAAACACUGGAACCACCUGUUACAAGAGUAUUUCAAGUGAGGAUGAGGAUGACCAUUCCAUGUAGAAAUUUUUUUUUUUUUUUUUUUUUCUGAGACAGGGUCUUACUUCAUUUGCCCAGGUUGGAGUGUACUGCUGCAAUCAGCCUCUCGAGUAGCUGGUAUCACAGGCACGUGCCACCACGCCCAGCUAAUUUUUACAUUUGUUGAGAGGUGUUUCACCAUGUUGGCCAGGCUGGUUUCGAACUCCUGGACUCAGGUAAUCCACCCAUCUUGGUCUCCCAAAGUGCUGGGAUUACAGACGUUAGCCACUGCACCUGGCUGAAAGAUAAUUUUUAAAGGAAGACAUGAUUGAUAGACCAAGUCAGCCAUUUGAAGGUCAGAACAUUUGAGGUAGGUGGGCCCCAGGGGCCAGUAAAGGCUUCAGGGUCAUAUAUAUGCAACUGAAAAAGUAAGUUAAAUGACGUGGCAGCAGCAGUGAACAAGACGCUGUUAGCUGUUAAGAUAAUUUACUUAGCCAAGAACAAAAGCUUUAUUUAAAAAAAUUGCUGAAUAAAGUUUUAUCUGCAGUGAAUCCCCUUAGUCAAACUCCAGAUUGGUGUUUUGGGGUAACUUAUCAAUAUUACAGCUUUCCUUCAACUCUGAAAAUAGUUGAAAGAAUUCCGGUAUAUUCUUUACUCUGAUCAACAUACUUUUUGGCUCAAAAAGUUUUCUAGUCUUACAGGCGUUUUCUAUUUCAGCCCUGGAAUGGGCCAUUUCUCCAAGGAUUGCUGGCUUCUUAGAAUAGGGAGUAUUACUUAGAAACUUAAGUCCAGUUGCUGAAUAUGCUCUUUACAGGGUAUUUCUAGGGCCUUUCAGGUGAAAGAAAAUUUGUACAUGUAUCAUAAAAACUGAACGCACAGUGGAUACUUUGAAGUUGAAUCAAACAAUGUUAUUUUUCCUACUGCUACUGCCGUCCGUAUUUGUAAUUAUUUUCAAAUAAGUGGAAUCAGUUGAUCCAACUAGGAAAGUAGAUGAGGUUGCUCUAUAGGAAUAAGAAUCCAUGAAUAAAAAUGGAGAUCUAAUUUUAGACUAAAACUUUUCAGCCCCUAAACAAAUGUCUCUGCUACCAAAUUUUAAUGGAUAUGUGUGAGAAUACAAGUAGUGUCUUUGGGUAGUGUCUUUAAACACAGGCUUUAGAGUCUGUCUACCACCUGUUGGUUCAGCAUCAGUCUUUUCAUCUGUAUUGCGAAAGAUCGUGGUGAACAUUAAUAAGGAAACAAAAGUACUUAGAGCCUAUGAGCACUUCCUAAACAUAAGAAAACCUAAAAUUUGUGAUUGGGAUUACUUUUUAAAUUGGUUUUAGAACUUUAUUUCUGAACUAGUUGGGGUUUUCUUGGUUCAAAGGCAAAAUUCCUCCUAGGUGUAAGGGAUGCAUUACUCAGUGUACAUAAGAACACUGAGACUAAGACUGGAUAAUAAAAUUAAACAUAUGCCUCGUUUUGAAGAUUUUAUGUGUAAAAAACAAAAAAAAAAUUGACCUUAACCUAAAGUGAGCUAGGUUUGAAAAUCUCAUCUCAUUCCUUUCUUGUUUUAUUUUAAUACAUGUGUUUUCAUAUGCUGUUUACUUUCUUUGGCCUUUGGCAGAACCCAGAAAUGAUCUAGGGUAAAACGAAAUGAGGUAUCGCUAUAUAUUUGGAUUUCUCAUGCUUCAGAAUACCCAAAUUGUCAUUAUUCAGGUUAUCCCUUCUAUCUCCCAACAUUUACCUGGAGCCUUGACACUGGUGUGGAUGUGACAUGGGUGUCUGUCUUGAGAUCAGAUGUGAUUUUAGACUUGGAUUAGGCCAGUCAACAAAGUUUUAUUUUUAUUAUCUUUGAGAUGAUUCUCACUAUGUUGCCUGGACUAGUGUCUAACUCCUGGGCUCAAGUGGUUGUCUCACCUCAACCUCCUGAGGUGCUAUGCUUACAAGUGGGAGCUGCCGCACUUAACUAUGGAUUUCAAAACUGGAGGCUGGAACUGUUGUCUUUGCUAUUCAUUUGGCUUGGUGAGUGGACUUAGCCACUUCACGGCAACUUGGAGAUGAAUAGCCCACUGUAUUUAACCUGCAUUUGCACUAUUUCAGCUCUGCUUGGCUGCCUUUUCUUUUACUUCUGCCACUGGGCUUUUGUGCAUGUGUUUUACUAGUUCAACAUAGGAUCUCCUUUUCAUCAGUACCUACUCUUUGGUUCUAUAAAUCUGAACUGGUUUUGAACCAGUUCAAAAUACUCUAGAAACACUUGCUUAUUAAUGAGUUUCCUAAUUUCCAGCACUGUGCUUGGAACUUGGUAAGUGUACAGAAAAGUUUUGGAUGUAUAGGUCAGUUAGGAUUUAUCUAGACCCAUUCAAUGUACCAACCAUAAUCCUGUGUGGGACUGUGUAGCAAGUCGAAUGAUUGAUUCUCAGUAGUUCAGUCUCUAAGGUCUUUUGUAGUUGUCAUAUUCCUGUAGAUUGAGAAAACCAAUGAAACAAAGCUGGAUUGUGUAUACAGUUAGCUCUUUCAUAAUGCAGGGGCUAGGGGCCCCAGCUUCCUUCAGUCAAAUCUAUGUAUAAGCUGAUUCCCCCAAAACUUGACAGCCUACUGUGGAAACUUUACCAAUAAGUCAUUUAACACACACUUUGUAUGUUAUGUGUAUUAUAUACUGUAAAAAGUAAGCUAGAGAAAAUGUUAAGCAAUCGGAAAUAUAUUAUGGCCAGGUGUGGUGGCUCAUGCCUGUAAUCCCAACACUUUGGGAGGCUGAGGCGGGCCAGUGACUUGAGGUUACAAGUUCGAGACCAGCCUGGCUAAUAUGGAGAAACCCUGCCUCUACUAAAAAUACAAAACUUAGCUGUAGGUGGUAGUGGUGUGUGCCUGUAGUCCAAGCUACUCAGGAGGCUGAGGCACAAGAAUUGAUUGAACUCUGGAGGUGGAGGUUGCAGUGAGCCCACAAGAAUUGACUGAACUCGGGAGGUGGAGGUUGCAGUGAGCCGAGAUAGUGCCACUGCACUCCAACCUGAGCAACAGAAUGAAACUGUCUGUGUGUGUGUGUGUGUGUAUGUAUAUGUAUGUGUAUGUAUAUUUACUCUCAGGUGGAACUGGAUUAUAACAGUCUCAAUCCUCACUGCCUUCAUGAAUAGCUGAGGAGGAGGGGGGUCUUGCUGUCACAGGGGUAGUAGAGACAGAAGUAAACCUGUAAGUGGACCCUCUUAGUUCAAAUUUGAUAUUCAAGAGUCAACUUAGUUGUUUUUUAAAGUCAAGGGAAGGCAUAUCAAUAGUUGCAGUUACCUAGUACUGCAUAACAAAACAACCUCCAAAACUUAAUGGCUUAAAACAAGCAAAAUUUUUCUGACUGGGCUUAGUUUGUUGCAGUCGUUUUCCAAAAUGACCAAAGACAUCAAAGCUUAAAUUACAUAUUGUAUGCCUGUUCAGGGAGAAAAACAUAUGCUUUUCCCCAUCAUUUUGGAAUCUUUUACUUGAAUUAUAGCUGGACAAUUGAUUUCCAGCUAUAAUUCAAGCUAUAACGUAGUGAACUCCCUCAGACAAAAAUGUCAAGCUUGAUUAGUAAAGGAACCUCAAGUGGUAUGUAUAAGGUGACCCUUAAGUACACGUGUUUUCAAAAGUUGGGUAUAAUGUAACUAGACUGAGAGGUUUCGAGAAAAACUUCAUUGCUAUUCCAUGUAUAGUUUUAAACUAGUGGGAUUUCAGUUUACAGUAUUAAUCAGCAAUUUGGGGAGAACUAAGUGUUCGUUUAACAUUAAGAUAAUAAAAAUAAUGCCUUAAUCAUACUUGAUUGAGAAUAUUAAUUCCCUUUUUAUGCAUAAGGAUGGAAGUUAAGUAACUUUAACAAUGACACAGUUGAGUUGUGUUGGAGCCAGCAUUUGGAUGGCCCUACACUUUGCACUGCCUUGUAGAUAUUUCUGUCACACAACUAGUGGUUAAAUAAGCAUGUUCUUUAGGCUAGAGCUUUCAGAGAUGAAAUAUUUUAGAGACCAGAGUUAAUCUAGAUUUCAUUUUAAACAAUAUUCAGAUAAUCUUUCCUUUUUCUCUCCCCUGCCCUGAAGAGUUUGUAUUUAUUAUAAUGUUGUAUAACACAGCCCCAAUACAAUGUGGCUUAUAUAGGUUUUUCUCUUAGGCUUAGACAGACUCUGGGACUGAUAUGGGAGCUUCAUGGUUCUCAGGCAGACUUUCAUUCUACUUUUUGUCUUUGGCAAGUUGGUUUAUUAUCAAGUGGUUGCUGGGGCUCUAUACAUCAUGUCCAGGUUCAAGGUACAGGAUGGGCUGAAGGAGGCUAAAGGCUACUGGCAUCCAACCUCUCCUGUAAAAAGAAGAACCUAUGGUUUAUGCUCACAGUGCUAAAAGUAGGAUAGUAAAUAAAAUAGAGCUGGGUGUGAAUGCCAAGGGAGGUUAGGAUGACAGCCACAUUGGCCACAUAUGUCGAAAUAAGUUGAUUUAGAAAAGGAUUAUUUGAUCAAGGAUAUCCUGGAACAUAAAGCAAAUAACUACAUUUUAGAAAUAAGUGAACAGGGCUAAGAAAAGUAAUUUUCUUUAAAUACGGCCCAAAAGGAUUAAUUAUGAUUGGAGUCCUGCUUUGCCCAAGGCUUUUUAUUUCAUUUUGCAUGAUAACCUUUCUCAGAACCAUGCAUGCACAAAUUAGGUUGAGACAAUGACUUAAAAGUGUAAAUGAAAUCUCAUUAGAAACAAAAACUUUCUGGUUUCUGACAUGUUUAAGGGGUGCUCAUUGUUACUCAACAAUGAUUUACUUAGGUAGUUAUUGUGAUGGGGGCGGUUCUAAUGGGAUUUCUUUUUCUGGUAGGUUUAGUGGCAACAUACAAGCUUGCCAUAAACAUUUCCUGGGUUUUAUCUUCUUGUAAAAGUGUUAUUCCACCUUUCUGAGUCUGGCUACCCCACAGAAUUCUUUUAUCCCUUUUACUCUUAGAUUACCUUGUCUGUAAUGAAACUUACCCUCUCUGAAGCCUGAGUUGUUCUUCUAAAGUAACACCACUACCACCUUCUUUAUUCUCAUGUUUUUGGGAGGAAUUGUCUACACUCACUGCUAUAUGUCCUCUAUCACCUAAGAAAGGUAUUUGCCCAUUACUGGAUUUUUUUUUCUUACAGAGAUCAAUAGUGAUCAAAUUGAACAGCCUAUGUCCUCAGGCUGUGUGUUUUGUGGCAAUGGAAAAAUGACAGCAAAAGAGGGAAAUAUCCUUGGAAUUUAGUUCCUUAAAUGGAGGUAUUUGCCCAAGUGACUGUCAGUUACAUAUUUGAGUUGCAAACAACGGGUUGCAUUUACCGGGUUUCAGAGUAGAAGCAUACUUAGGAAAGGUGGUAGGUGUUCUUGGGCUCUUCAGUGGGGACAGAGGAUUGCUUCCACUCUUAGUUACUGGGGUAUCUUGUCACCCCAGAGACCCAGAGCCAGAAUAUCAACACUUUUGAGUGAUUGCAGUUUUGUGACAACAUAAUACUGGUUCUCUCAGCCUCCUUCAUUGGAUUACCUUCCUCUCUGCUCCAUUUCAUCCAGUUCCAUAUUUUCGUUUGUCACUUCAAAGCUAAUAUUACCAUAACAAGUUUACAAAUAAUCAGACUUCCUGGUUACUUGUUAAUACUCAAUAAGAUAGCCUGCUUGCCCAUUUUGAAUAAUAUCAAUACAUUUCCAGACAAAACAUUAGUCAUUUCCCCUCAGUUUAAGUGCUGUCAAUCAGCUCUCCGUUAGGUACAAUGGCGAAAACACUCAUCCAGGAUCUUGGAUAUUUAGUGAAGUAGACGUGAAAAUUGGAUAACUACUCAUCAGAGUUUGAAGUGAUUAGGAAGGAAUUAACUCAGCCAGAGGAAAUCUGGGAUUUGAAUAGGGCUUUGAAGAAUGAAAGGUUUACAGAGGAUUUGGGAAGGUAAAUUGGAGGCUGCGAGGACAAGGAGAUGUAUGACUGGCACUCGCUCAAGGUUGAGUGGAACGAGUCAAAAUAAGUAGGACCCAUUCUGUGGAGGGCUUGUCAUGCAAGGGUAAGGAAUUGGAAUGUAUACAAUUGGAGGCGAAUAGAAGUUUUCUGUCAUGUUUUAAGAGUAAAACUGAAGGCCAUGUGUAUGAGUAUGGAUCAGGUGAUUGGGCCACCCAAGAACUUAGAUGAGAGAACUGAAUUAGGCUGCUGGCAGAACAGAAAGGACGGAGACAGCUGAUGGACGGUGCUUGGAUCCACAAUUGUGUUUGUACUACAGUUAAAAAAAAGCGCUAAGCACUCAUUAUAAAGCACUUGCUUUAAGCUGUUACACAGAUUGGUCACUAGGAGGCAUCAGUUCAUCAACUACUAAGGCGAAAAGGAAGGCAGCUCUGGACACCCACCUAAGAAGUCUGGAUAGUUCUGUGUUAAUACUUAACGUUUUCAACUCAAGGACUUUUGGAAACUAGAAUCUAGAAUAUUUCUUCUGAAUAGUACUUCAAAGAUGAAAUAAGGCUAAGAAGUCUAAACUGCACUCUGUGAGACUAUUUGUUUAUUUAUUUAAUUAUUUAUUUUGAGACAGAUUCUCGCUCUGUUGCCCAGGCUGGAGUGCAGUGGCGUGAUCUUGGCUCACUGUAACCUUCACCUCCCUGGCUCAAGCAAUUCUCCUGCCUCAGCCUCCCGAGUAGCUGGGAUUACAGGCGCUGUGGGUUUUUUUUUUUUUUGUAUUUUUAGUAGAGACGGGGUUUCACCAUGUUGGCCAGACUUGUGUCGAGCUCCUGACCUCAGGCAAUCCGCCUGCCUCAGCCUCCCAAAGUGUUGGGAUUACAGGCGUGAGCCACCGCGCCCAGCCUUGGUUAUCUUUUAUACCCUGAUGAGGGUAACGUGACAUGUUCAUAAUUUACUGGGCUUUAACUUUUUCUUGAAAGAUGUUUGACCUUUGGUCUAUCCAAAUCUUUAAUAAUGAUCAUUGUCAUGAGUUUCUACUGUAUAUUGCAAAUUGGUUUACAGAUCAGAAUUUUGUAAUCAUUAUGAAUUAAACACUUAAUAACUUUCCAA